UUCCCAAGACUACCAACAAAUCUUCCCUCUUGCUGUGGGGAAAUGAGUCUUCCUUCAACAUCUUCAGUGAAAAUAUCAAGGCCCUUCGGCAUGGGCUCCGCCAGCAUCUCUCGCCGAUGCCUUCACUCCAAAUCCUCUCUUCUUUCUUCCCUUGUCUCUGUGUCUGUAGACAACUGGUCUCUUUUCAGGGCUAACUCUGAUUUGGGUUCUCCUUUCUCCAGAGCCUUCUUUAAUCCCUUAGGCACUGUGGUUUUCCCCUCAGUCCAUUCAGCAUGAGCUCUCCAUUUCUUUUUUUUCUUUUUCUUUUUUUUGAGACGGAGUCUCAGUCUGUCGCUCAGGCUGGAAUGCAGUGGUGUGAUCUUGGCUCACCUGCAACCUCCGCCUCCUGGGUUCAAGUGAUUCCCCUGCCUCAGCCUCCCGAGUAGCUGGGACUAUAGGCACCAGCCACCACGCUCAGCUAAUUUUUGUAUUUGUAGUAGAGAUGGGGUUUCACCAUAUUGGCCAGGCUGGUCUCGAACUCCUGACCUCAUGAUCCGCCCACCUCGGCCUCCCAAAGUGCUGGGAUUACAGGCGUGAGCCACUGCACCCGGCCACUCUCCAUUUCAUGACUGCUUUGUGUCAGGAUCUGUGCCAGGCCCCAGGGAUACAGCAGUGACCAAACGGACACACAGUCCCUGCUCUCUGAGCUUAGCCUUUCUUCUAUUCUCACAAAAUAAAACAAAACAAAACAACAGUAAACAUCGCAAACACCCUUCACAGAUGCUUCAUCUUUCUCCUUUGCUUUGUUAAACCUUUCUAGAACGUCUUCUGUUUUCAUUCUUUUCACUGCCUUUCCCUGUGUUCACUCUUCAGCCCUUUGUCACCUGGCUUCUGCUUCCACCUCAACAAUUUGUUCACCUUGAUGUUACUAUCAUUCUUCUAAUGAUAAACCUAGAGACCUUUGCCGCAUUCAGCACUGCGGACCACCCCCUUUAGAAACUGCAUGUCCCUCCUUGCUUGCCUGGUACUUUCUUUUCCUACUUCUCCUCCUCUGUCUUCUCUGUCCCUUUUUCUUUGCUUCUUCAUUCCCUUCCCUCAGAGGUGGUCCCUGUGUUCCCCCUGGACUUUUUCUUUUUCUCCUGUGCAUGCUUUCCUUGGUGCUCAGAUGCUCCUACAUUUAUAAGUAGUAAUUCACUUAACAAAUAUUUGAGUGUCUACUAUGUGCUCGACACUGUUCUAAGUGCUGGGGAUAUUGUAGUGAGUAAAACAGGCAAGAAUACCUGACCUCAUGGAGCUUACAGUCUAGUGUAAGGGAACUCUGAAAGUGAAUCAUAAAAUAAGCAAAUUAUAGACAAAGUAUCUGAUGCUAUCCAGUCUUACACUAUCCGAACUCUCCCUAUAAAAGAGCUCAGGAACUGAAUGGAUUCAGGUAAAUUUUUGGAUGAAUCCUUUGCUCUAUGAACUCUUACUACAUGGUAUCCAAAACUCAGGACUCAAUCAAAUUUGGAUAAUGUAUUAUGCCUUGUUAUCUGAACUUGUUUUCACUUUGUGAAAUCAGAAACUGAAUGAAUAAAUGUGGAUAUCACAGGAUAGGUUAAUGGGUGACGUGCUAAUGAGACAAAAACAAAUAAAUAUAUCAGGGAAGGGAGGCAAUAGGAAGUGUUCGUGCUGGGAUGGGGAAAGGCAACAUUUCAGUAGCAGCCUGAAAGAGGCGAGGCAAUUCAGAUACCUAGGAAGGGCACAGAGGAUCCAUCUCUCCCACGUUGAGAAUCUCUCCUGCCUGCUGUGCUCUUCCCCCUUUUUUUUUUUUUUUUUUUUGACCGAGUCUCACUCUGUUACCCAGGCUAGAGUGCAGUGAUGUGAUCUUGGCUCACUGCAACCUCCACCUCCCAGCUUCAAGUGAUUCUUCUGCCUCAGCCUCCCGAGUAGCUGGGAUUACAGGUGUGCCCCACCACGCCCAGCUAAUAUUUGUAUUUUAGUAGAGACGGGGUUUCACUAUGUUGGCCAGGCUGGUCUGGGACUCCUGGCCUCAAGUGAUCCAUGAUCUGCCUGCCUCACACUCCCAAAGUGCUGGGAUUACAGGCGUGAGCCACCGCGCCCGGUCUCCUGCCUCUUCUGUCAUCACAUCACUGCUGCUGGGAAAGGUUUUCUGAUUUUAAGGACUCUUGUAAUUAGAUUGGACGCACCUAGAUGAGCCAGGACACUCUCUCCAUCUCAAGGUCCCUAACCUUAAUCACAUCUACAAAGUGCCUUUCGCCAUGCAAGGUAACACAGCCACAGGUUCCAGGGAUGAGUGUGUCGACGUCUUUGGGGUCUGUUAUUUUGCCUACACCCCACAUUCUCAUUCUCAAGCAUUUUCAAGUGGGUUUCCAUUUUCUUUACUCCAAGAUGUGGCUCUAACCUCCCCUCCAGUCUUAUCUUCCACUGUUCUCUUUUAUAAUCUCUGCUCCAGCCAAAUACUCUCAGAAUAUUUCCUAUUCUGUGUGCCUUUUCACGUAUUUUUUCUUCUGCCUUGAGUGCCAGCUCUGUCUGUUAAACUCCUGUUGCUGGUUUAAGGCUUCUCCAGCUCUCUUCUUCCCUCCUGUUUACCACUCCCCUCUACCUACUGUCAGUGAAACCACAGCCACCCUCAAUCAGUCAGCAAACACUGACUCUCCAUCAUGUCCUGGACGCUGGGGAUACAGACGUGAAUCAGAAAACUUAGGCCAUGGAUAUUUCAAGUACAUGUCAGCAGUGUGCUGGCUCUUUGGACGUCACCUUUAUGACACUCUGCAGUAUCCCAUCGGGCUGAUCGCCUCCAGCUGGGGCGGGACACCCAUUGAAGCCUGGUCAUCUGGACGGUCACUGAAAGCCUGUGGGGUCCCUAAACAAGGGUCCAUUCCAUACGAUUCUGUAACUGGUCCCAGUAAGCACUCUGUUCUCUGGAAUGCCAUGAUCCAUCCACUGUGCAAUAUGACUCUGAAAGGGGUAGUAUGGUACCAGGGGGAGUCCAAUAUAAAUUAUAACACGGAUCUGUACAAUUGCACAUUCCCUGCACUCAUCGAAGACUGGCGUGAAACCUUCCACCGUGGUUCCCAGGGGCAGACGGAGCGUUUCUUCCCAUUUGGACUUGUCCAGUUAUCUUCAGAUUUGUCUAAGAAGAGCUCAGACGAUGGAUUUCCCCAGAUCCGUUGGCAUCAAACAGCAGACUUCGGCUAUGUCCCCAACCCAAAGAUGCCCAAUACUUUCAUGGCUGUAGCUAUGGAUCUCUGUGAUAGAGACUCGCCUUUUGGCAGCAUCCACCCUCGAGAUAAACAGACUGUGGCUUAUCGGCUGCAUUUGGGGGCCCGUGCUCUGGCUUAUGGUGAGAAGAAUUUGACCUUUGAAGGACCACUGCCUGAGAAGAUAGAACUCUUGGCUCACAAGGGGCUGCUCAAUCUCACAUAUUACCAGCAAAUCCAGGUGCAGAAAAAGGACAACAAGAUAUUUGAGAUCUCCUGUUGCAGUGACCAUCGAUGCAAGUGGCUUCCAGCUUCUAUGAACACCGUCUCCACCCAGUCCCUGACCCUGGCGAUCGAUUCUUGUCAUGGCACUGUGGUUGCUCUCCGCUAUGCUUGGACCACGUGGCCUUGUGAAUAUAAGCAGUGUCCCCUAUACCACCCCAGUAGUGCCCUGCCAGCCCCUCCCUUCAUUGCUUUCAUUACAGACCAGGGUCCUGGACAUCAGAGCAAUGUUGCUAAAUGACUGUUUCAGUAUGAUCAGAACUUAGAUAUAAGGAUGGGUCCUUCAGAUUUUAGCAUUUAGGAGUUUCAAUAAUAACCAUUGCUUUUAAAGGAAAUUAAUAGAAAGCCUCAUUGAAUGGCUUUCAGCUAGCACAUGGCUGUUUCUAUAUUCUGAUGAGCCCAGGCUUAUAGGUAACUUGAAAUGCUUGCUUUUUGUUCCCUAGUUGGUCUAAGGGUCUGUAUUGGACUAAUUCUGAACUACAGACAAAUUGGACCUCAAUGUCAUUUACUUCCCUCAUAUUAAUGGGAGUGAAAUGUCUAAUACUUUUGCCCCUUUUUAUCCAGAGUUGUGGGAAUCUCAGGAUUGGAAGAGAUUUUAAAGGCCACAUAGGCCAGCUAGUGUUCAUGUGUUCUUUAUAAAAUUUCUCCCAUCCAAGUACUAACCAGGCCCGACCCUGCUUAGCUUCCGAGAUCAGAUGAGAUCAGGCGCGUUCAGGGUGAUAUGGCCGUAGACGUCUUUACAAAAUUCCUGACAGGUGGUUACUGAAUCUCUCUAUGAACUUUCCAUUCAAAACUUUCCAAGUUUUUCCUUAUGUGGAACCGAAAUCUUUCUUUCUCCCGUGAAACUUUACUACUAUCAGAUAAUUGAAGACAGAUCUCUUUGUAUUCUCUUCAAGCCCAAACCAAUUCUGUUCCUUCAAUCUAAAUAGUGGUAAUAUGAAUGUUUAAGAAAUGAAAUAAGAAACAUGUGCAGGCACUUUGGAAGGUGCUAAGUGACUGCCCUAAGGAAUGAAAAGCAAGGGCCAGGUGGGAGUAGCCCAGCGAAGGCACUUGGGCUGCCAGGAACAGGAGGCGUGGGAAACUCUGGCUUAGGAAAACAUGAACACAGGGGCAACAGAGGCAAACUGUUGUUCGAGUUAAAUAUAAAUCUCAGGCUCUUUAAAGGUAAAAGGUUUAAGGAUAAUCCAUUUGGAAGAAGAAAAGAGUGAGGCUGAAAGUAAAGCCACAUGACAAGCAUAUAAAAAAAAAUGCAGAUGAUACAAAUAUGAAAGAGGCCUUCAGUGUUUGUUUAUUAAGAAUCUUAAUGCAGUUUACUGAUGGAUUAAAAACAGCUAACAUUGUCUGAAAAUUAUGUUACCUAUAAGAAGUUGGAAAUAAAUAAAAGCAUAAUCACUAGUGAUGUGUAUGUAUUUAUAUCCACUUGCAAACUGUCCUUGAAGCAUGUGAAAAGGAGUAAGAAUACUAUCUAUGGGUAGCUUUCCUCCCCUUAAUGUGAAAAAUGAGAACUAAAGCAAAAAGCAUCACUCACUGUACAUAUACAAUGUAUUUUACGUAGUGUAAAAAAUAUGGUUUAGAUAGUGAAUAUAUUAAUGAAAUCAUAUGUAAAUUUAUUUUUAGUGGCUGAAUAAUUUAAAACAUUAUGUGGAAUUCACUAUGUUUCCCCCAAUUUAGGAACUUUUUACUGUGUGAAAAUGAAAUUUAUAAUACUCUGUAGGGUGAAUGAUGGUUUUUGCUUUAGUUCUACCCCUCUGUAGAGUUCCAAGGGGUUCUGGUGUAGCUCCAAACAGCAGGAAUAACUUUGUCAGUGCCAAGAUUUUAUUUAGUUAAAAAACAAAAAAUCUACACACUUUACAAGGAACGUUGGCUCCCCUGAGGACUUCCUAGCAUUCAACUCGUUCAGUUAACCCCUAUUGCCCAUGCUUUGACCUCUCAUGCAUCUGGCCCCAUAGAAACCAUGAACCUUGUAACAGAUUGAUGCCUGAGAAAAAGUCAAUCUACCCGUCCACUCCUCCACUCCCAAUACACAUACCCCCAUGGGCUGUUCUAAUUCGGGGGCAGCCAGAGGUAGCCAAGAACUCUAAGUCCAGAUUCCUUUCACCUCCAGGAACCUAGAGUACAUAGUGUGAAAAAUACGGUUCAGGCAAUGAUUAUGUUAAUGACGCCAUGCACAUUCAUUUUUAGUGGCUGAGUAAUUUAAAACAUGAUGUGGGAAUUCACUGCAUUUCCCCAAAUGUAAGAACUUUUUAGUUUUAAAAUGAAAUUUAUAGUCACUGUAGAAAAUUUGGACACUAAAGUAUAAGCAAGUAAAAAUCACCCCCAAAUUCAUCAUUCAGAGAAACACUAUUUUGCUGAACCAUUCACUUGACUUGAGUUAUAUAAUUUUAUACAGUACAUAUUAUUUUGUAAUCUGUGUUUUUGACUUACUUACUUUACCAAAAUAAUUUUCUUAUGUAAAUAAUAGAAUAUAGAUUUAGAGUGUUUCAGUUUGUGGAAGCCUCAUUUUAUUUAACCAAUUUCCUAUUAAUGGACAUAUAGAUUUUUAACAAUUUUCUACUAUUAAAAUAAUACUGUAAUGAAUAUCACAUGCAAACAUCAUACCACACUCGUCCAGUUAUUUCUUAGGGUUCUUAACAUGGAAGAGGAUAAAUAUAUAUUUAAAAUUUAGAUAUCUACAGCUUAACCCUCCCAAAGGAUUAAACAACUUACAUUCUCACCAAGGUAGUCCUUUUUUUGCCCUCACCCUCAUUGACACUGGAUGUUGUCAAAUUUAAAAAAAAUCCUUAACAAUCUGAUAGAUGAAAAGAUAGUUUAAGUAUACUAAGGCAGUGUUUUUCAAGGUGUUUUUGUUUUUGUUUUUGAGUUGGAGUUUUGCUCUGUUGCCCAGGCUGGAGUGCAGUGGCGCGGUCUCGGCUCACUGCAACCUCUGCCUCCCGGGUUCAAGCGAUUCUUCCUGCCUCAGCCUCCCGAGUAGCUGGGACUACAGGCGCGUGCCACCACGCCUGGCUAAUUUUUUGUAUUUUUAUUAGAGACCGACUUAGCCAGGAUGGUCUCGAUCUCCUGACCUCUUGAUCCACCCGCCUCAGCCUCCCAAAGUGCUGGGAUUACAGGCGUGAGCCACCGUGCCCAGCUUUUCAAGUUUCUUAAAUCCAUGAUCCAUAGUAAAAACAUUUUACACAUAUCUUCAUACAAGUAUAUGUAUAUGUGGUAUACGUACACACUAUAGUUGUAUAUGCAUUAUAGCUGAAAAACCAGUUCAACCUUUCUACAUGUGGUAUGUUCCAAAAAUUUUAAAUGUCUUUCUAAAAUGAGGCUCUUUUAAUACGGGUAUUACUCAGGCUGUAAUAGUGGGAAAAUAUUUGUUAUAUGAUAAAAGCAGCAUAUAUCAUUUCUGUGUAAAUGCCAGUAUGCUCAAGCCAUUUAUGCAGAGAAAAAAAGAAAAACACUGCAUUAACAUUUUAAGCAGUCCCCUUCCCGAUUUGCUAUUAUACAAAGUUUGUUUCUUUUACAUUGUAAAGUGUAUACAACUUAUAAAAAGACUAUACUCAAAAUCAUAAAAUACCAGUUAACUUAGCUUCUCAGUUUACAGUGGCCAGUGUGGUGUGCUCUAAACACUGCUGCCUGAUCCCUCCCUCUGCUGGUCAGAUUUAUUACUAUAAAGUACCAAUCCCAUUUGUGUUGUCCUCAAUUGGCAAUUAUGAAUGGCAGUGCAUUAACCAUUCAAUUCUCACCACUCCAUCCCCAUUCUUCUACUUCUGGGUCCUUUUGUCCCUCCCUUUCCAGACAGCCCUUGGUAACCUGCUGCUGGGUAACUAAGGCAUCCCACAGGUAGUGUUGAGGUGUUAGGUGAUAGAGUAAACCUCUACCUUAAUGCUAUUAACAGGGUCCAAAAAUCCAGUUGCAUGGAACAUGGAGUUAUAUUAUUACAUGGCUAAUGAAAAGACAGGACUAAGUCUGUUAUAGAGUAUGGGACUAACCCCCAAUUAUAUGUGAAUUUGUGUUAUCAUAUGGUUUCAGUGUACUGAGCUAAAAAGCACAUUAUCUGAGGUGCAAUACAAAGGUUAAAGAGGUUAAAGAUCCCC